GAGACACCCAGUGCUGGCGAGAGGCAGAGAAGCUGGAUCCUCAUGCAUCACUGAGGGUGAGAGACGGCGCAACCACUCUGGAGACUGUUUGGAAGUUCCUGUAAAAACUAAACAUGUAACUGUUCUGUGACCCGGCAGUUGCUCUCCUGGGCAUUUAUCCCAGUGGAUUGAAGACGCUGUUCACAGACAAACCUGAACUUGAAUGUUCGGGAUCGCCAGCACAGGACCUGACUACUGUUACAUGCAGUGACUGGAAGCCUGUCCUGGGAGCCGAGGAGCAGUGCGAAAGCCGGGCACAGAAGGCCGCCUCCUGCACGUUCCCGGAUCAUGCUCUGGAGAGCACAGCCACGGCGUCGGGAUAGCACAGCCACGGCGUCGGGAUAGCACAGCGGCUGCCGUUGAGGGGCUGCCAGUGGCUGUAAGGGGCGCCUCGGGUGCUCGUGCCCUGGGACAUCUGGAUCUGGACUCCAUCAUGUCCCUCUCCUGGUGCGGCGUUGACCUUGGGUCCUCGUGAUGUUACCACCAGAGGAAGUGGUGAAGGGCACAGAGGGUCUCUCUACAGUUGUUUCUUACAGCUGCAAUGUGAAUUCACAAUUUUCUCAAAGUAAGUUUAAUUAAAAAACAACAACAACAACAAAUGCAAACAGAAGCCUCCCCCAAGCACGUCAUUAACUGCAUUGGUAGAAAAGAAUCACUCACUACGCGUAAACGCUACACAAGUUGGAGACAGAUCCAGGGGCCUCAGAUGCCUCGGUGUGACUUCAUCGCUUCCGAGUUAGGAGACUGGCUCACUGAUACCACUCUUUGGACCACAGUUACAUUUUCACUAUUGUCUCCUUGUUGGUCUUGGGUGAGACGGAAUCAGCUGCGUCCGCUGGGACUUGUGACCUGGGGCCUGUGCUGUGAGAACGUCUACUCGGGAGGCUCUGCUGGCCCUGGGCCCUCACUUGGGGUGGGUGCUGUUUCCUACGGACGCGCCCAGGUGCCCUCUCUCCAGCCAGCUCCUCCCACUGCAAGAUCAUUGGUUGCAGAGUGAGGAGAGAUCCCCCUAACUCCACCGAACGAUACACACGUUGGAUCAACCAGCUGACGCCGGAGCAGCUCCUAACCCAGGUUUUCACCUCAAAUGGCCCCACGGUGAUCAUGCCCACCUGGUUCUGCUCGCGAGCGUGGUUCUCCCACGUGGGCCCCUUUAACGAGGGAGGUCAGGGCGUCCCGGAGGACCUGCUGUUCUUCUACGAGCACCUCAGGAAGGGCGGCGGCGUCAUCCGCGUGGACCAGAGUCUCCUGCUGUAUCGCCACCACCCACAGGCGGCCACGCACUGCGUCCUCGAGACGACCAUCUGGACCCACCGCGUCCGCUUCCUGGAAGAGCAGGCCCUGCCCCGCUGGGCGGCCUUCACCAUCUGGAACGCUGGCAAGCAGGGGCGCCGGCUGUACCGCAGCUUGACUGCCGGCAGCCAGCGCAAGGUGGUGGCAUUCUGUGACGUGGACGAGAACAAGAUCAGGAAAGGCUUCUAUUGCCACGAGGACUCUCAGGAAAGACCCAAGCCCCGAAUCCCCAUCCUGCACUUCCGAGCCGCCCGGCCACCCUUCGUCAUCUGCGUGAAGCUGGACCUCACAGGGGGCGCCUUUGAGGACAACCUGAGGUCACUGCACUUGCAGGAGGGCCAGGACUUCCUUCACUUCAGCUGACGGACCCAUGGCAGCUGCUCCCAGUGCAUCCCAGGCCAGCAGGAGCUUUGUGAGCUGCAGGCAUGGCGAUGGUGCGCCUGUUCCACACCCAGCAGGCGCAACCAGAGUCUCAUGUGUGCCGACCACAGGAGCCAAGCCUUUUCCACUGUGUGGACUCAUGUGGCCAAGGCUAGGCCUGGUCACCCAGGACCCUCACCACGUGACCCCAGCCAAUCGGGACAGUUCAAGGAGGAGGAGACCCCUAUUACACAGGUUGGAAUAAAAUAUUUAAAUCUCGUAAAAAUGUAACCCAAGGCUCUUUUAGGGUAUAAAGACCAUUGGCCACCAGGUCAAACACAACAACAGUAGUGUGUUAACCCCACACUCCUGUGUGGCCAGGUCGUCACACACAUCCCGUGAAGAGCUGUCUGCUAAACACACAGCACGGACUGUCACAGUCCUGGUCUUGUGGUCCUGGUGACCUCACAAGCCUCACAGAUGCGGUGGCACCUCCCAGUUCUUGGCCUGCCCAUGUUCCUGUGUCCAGGCCCCAUCCCCACCUGAGAGCAGGCCAGGGAGCCACCCUAAUCUACACCACGCACAUGGCACCCCUGGGCUCCUCACAUAGGGAAAGGGUUGCUCACCCAAGCCCUUGGGCCUCUGAGUGGCCACACCUGGGGCUGCUUUGGUGCUGCUGGCCGUGGUUCUGCACCUCAAGCCCUAUGAGCACAGCACAGGUCCCAGAGAUGGGUGUGGGUUGCUACCACAGUGAAAUUUUUAUACACGUUCCCCUCACCAGCUUUGGGAUGGAUCAGCACGAGCUCAGACACAGAGACAAAGGUAGCCUCCUGCCCUUUGCCUAAAAACCCAAGUGUGGACUCUGCCCAGGCUCUCCUAAGACAGUGUAAUUAUUUCAAGAAUGGUAUUUAUUUCCCACAUUACUGUAGAGGCACACAUUGGACUCUGACGAUUCCCCUUGCAGCAGACAUUUGUGAAGCUGCUGGUCGGCACACCCAUCAAUCAGUGACUCCUGCACUGCAGAGGGGCCACAUGCACGAUGCUCACGUGUGCACAGGGGGGAGGACAGCACCCCCACCAGGCAGACGGGCCCAGAAACAGCAUCUGCCCAGCACUCCAGACCAUGCCUGCCACCAGGGCUUCUCAGUUCUCUAGCAUUUGAACCUCUGAUUUAACAUUCAUCUCUCUCCAAGACUGGGUGGGGCACUGCCUGUGGCCAGACGUCUCCCACAGCAGGGACAGCACCAGGCAAGAAGGGGGCCUGGUCUCCAGGCAGGAGGAGUGCAGCCCACCUCCCCUCUGGCUGACCCCUGGGCAGUGAGCCUUUCCAUCACCCCUACACACAUCAGGCUCAGAGACAAAAGGCAGGAACUUCUUGGUACAUGAUUUUAUAGGAAGCACAUUUGUGUUCAAGUGAAGGCAGAGGCGUCCACCCCAAGUCACCAGAGCGCAGGUGCAGAGAGGAAAAGCUGUCAGCUAGUGCCAGCCUCCAAGGGCCAGCGCUACCCUUCAACAGCUGGAGGCACCACUGUGCGAGGCUUUCCACACCGGCCUCCCUCAGGAACAAGACAUCCUCACCAGGCAGGGGUGAGGUAUGGGCUCCAGGACUGGCUUCAGCAGGCACCAGGCUGAAGAAGAGACAAGACAAGCUCAGGCUGGUCAGCUCCAACACACACCAUUCCCAGCCAGGGGACCCUCACCCCUCUGGGCCCUGUGUGGGGACUGACACGGUUCCUGCAGGAAACCAUUUGUGCCGUUUCCCACACACCCGGCAGCCUGAGCUAUGUGGCUGACAGGUGCUCAUGACUAACGUGUCCUCGGAAGGGCACCCCAUCUGGGGAGCGGGAAGGGAGGUUCACUGCACUGCUCUUAACCUGCAUUCACACGUUUGAAAUUUUUCCUAAUAAAAAUGUAAAAAGCA